CUUCCCCUUCUCCCAUCCCUCUCUCGGCCACAGCGUCUUGUUAGUCCUCUCCCUGUACUCCGCAAUAUUUUCUUUCUUUCUCCCUCCUCUCCUCCAUUUGUUGUUUGAUGUUUCCCACUCUUUGAGGAAGGAUGGUUGAUUUGGAGAGCGAAGUGCCCCCUCUGCCUCCCAGGUACAGGUUUCGAGAUUUGCUGCUAGGGGACCAAGGAUGGCAAAACGACGACAGGGUACAAGUUGAAUUCUAUAUGAAUGAAAAUACAUUUAAAGAAAGACUAAAAUUAUUUUUCAUAAAAAACCAGAGAUCAAGUCUAAGGAUACGCCUGUUCAAUUUUUCUCUCAAAUUACUAAGCUGCUUAUUAUACAUAAUCCGAGUACUACUAGAAAACCCUUCACAAGGAAAUGAAUGGUCUCAUAUCUUUUGGGUGAACAGAAGUCUACCUUUGUGGGGCUUACAGGUUUCAGUGGCAUUGAUAAGUCUGUUUGAAACAAUAUUACUUGGUUAUCUUAGUUAUAAGAUAUUCUGGCCUUCCUUAAGGAAUCUAUUUGUCCCAGUCUUUCUGAACUGUUGGCUUGCCAAACAUGCCUUGGAAAAUAUGAUUAAUGAUCUACACAGAGCCAUUCAGCGUACACAGUCUGCAAUGUUUAAUCAAGUUUUGAUUUUAAUAUCUACAUUACUAUGCCUUAUCUUCACCUGCAUUUGUGGGAUCCAACAUCUGGAACGAAUAGGAAAGAAGCUGAAUCUCUUUGACUCCCUUUAUUUCUGCAUUGUGACGUUUUCUACUGUGGGCUUCGGGGAUGUCACUCCUGAAACAUGGUCCUCCAAGCUUUUUGUAGUUGCUAUGAUUUGUGUUGCUCUUGUGGUUCUACCCAUACAGUUUGAACAGCUGGCUUAUUUGUGGAUGGAGAGACAAAAGUCAGGAGGAAACUAUAGUCGACAUAGAGCUCAAACUGAAAAGCAUGUCGUCCUGUGUGUCAGCUCACUGAAGAUUGAUUUACUUAUGGAUUUUUUAAAUGAAUUCUAUGCUCAUCCUAGGCUCCAGGAUUAUUAUGUGGUGAUUUUGUGUCCUACUGAAAUGGAUGUACAGGUUCGAAGGGUACUGCAGAUUCCAAUGUGGUCCCAACGAGUUAUCUACCUUCAAGGUUCAGCCCUUAAAGAUCAAGACCUAUUGAGAGCAAAGAUGGAUGACGCUGAGGCCUGUUUUAUUCUCAGUAGCCGUUGUGAAGUGGAUAGGACAUCAUCUGAUCACCAAACAAUUUUGAGAGCAUGGGCUGUGAAAGAUUUUGCUCCAAAUUGUCCUUUGUAUGUCCAGAUAUUAAAGCCUGAAAAUAAAUUUCACAUCAAAUUUGCUGAUCAUGUUGUUUGUGAAGAAGAGUUUAAAUACGCCAUGUUAGCUUUAAACUGUAUAUGCCCAGCAACAUCUACACUUAUUACACUACUGGUUCAUACCUCUAGAGGGCAAGAAGGCCAGCAAUCGCCAGAACAAUGGCAGAAGAUGUACGGUAGAUGCUCCGGGAAUGAAGUCUACCACAUUGUUUUGGAAGAAAGUACAUUUUUUGCUGAAUAUGAAGGAAAGAGUUUUACAUAUGCCUCUUUCCAUGCACACAAAAAGUUUGGCGUCUGCUUGAUUGGUGUUAGGAGGGAGGAUAAUAAAAACAUUUUGCUGAAUCCAGGUCCUCGAUACAUUAUGAAUUCUACAGACAUAUGCUUUUAUAUUAAUAUUACCAAAGAAGAGAAUUCAGCAUUUAAAAACCAAGACCAGCAGAGAAAAAGCAAUGUGUCCAGGUCGUUUUAUCAUGGACCUUCCAGAUUACCUGUACAUAGCAUAAUUGCCAGCAUGGGUACUGUGGCUAUAGACUUGCAAGAUACAAGCUGUAGAUCAGCAAGUGGCCCUACCCUGUCUCUUCCUACAGAGGGAAGCAAAGAAAUAAGAAGACCUAGCAUUGCUCCUGUUUUAGAGGUUGCAGAUACAUCAUCGAUUCAAACAUGUGAUCUUCUAAGUGACCAAUCAGAAGAUGAAACUACACCAGAUGAAGAAAUGUCUUCAAACUUAGAGUAUGCUAAAGGUUACCCACCUUAUUCUCCAUAUAUAGGAAGUUCACCCACUUUUUGUCAUCUCCUUCAUGAAAAAGUACCAUUUUGCUGCUUAAGAUUAGACAAGAGUUGCCAACAUAACUACUAUGAGGAUGCAAAAGCCUAUGGAUUCAAAAAUAAACUAAUUAUAGUUGCAGCUGAAACAGCUGGAAAUGGAUUAUAUAACUUUAUUGUUCCUCUCAGGGCAUAUUAUAGACCAAAGAAAGAACUUAAUCCCAUAGUACUGCUAUUGGAUAACCCCCUAGAUGACUUACUCAGGUGUGGAGUGACUUUUGCUGCUAAUAUGGUGGUUGUGGAUAAAGAGAGCACCAUGAGUGCCGAGGAAGACUACAUGGCAGAUGCCAAAACCAUUGUGAACGUGCAGACACUCUUCAGGUUGUUUUCCAGUCUCAGUAUUAUCACAGAGCUAACUCACCCCGCCAACAUGAGAUUCAUGCAAUUCAGAGCCAAAGACUGUUACUCUCUUGCUCUUUCAAAACUGGAAAAGAAAGAACGGGAGAGAGGCUCUAACUUGGCCUUUAUGUUUCGACUGCCUUUUGCUGCUGGGAGGGUGUUUAGCAUCAGUAUGUUGGACACUCUGCUGUAUCAGUCAUUUGUGAAGGAUUAUAUGAUUUCUAUCACGAGACUUCUGUUGGGACUGGACACUACACCAGGAUCUGGGUUUCUUUGUUCUAUGAAAAUCACUGCAGAUGACUUAUGGAUCAGAACUUAUGCCAGACUUUAUCAGAAGUUGUGUUCUUCUACUGGAGAUGUUCCCAUUGGAAUCUACAGGACUGAGUCUCAGAAACUUACUACAUCUGAGUCUCGAAAAAUAGCAUCACAAUCUCAAAUAUCUAUCAGUGUAGAAGAGUGGGAAGACACCAAAGACUCCAAAGAACAAGGGCACCACCGCAGCAACCACCGCAACUCAACAUCCAGUGAUCAGUCGGACCAUCCCUUGCUGCGGAGAAAAAGCAUGCAGUGGGCCCGAAGACUGAGCAGAAAAGGCCCAAAACACUCUGGUAAAACAGCUGAAAAAAUAACCCAGCAGCGACUGAACCUCUACAGGAGGUCAGAAAGACAAGAGCUUGCUGAACUUGUGAAAAAUAGAAUGAAACACUUGGGUCUUUCUACAGUGGGAUAUGGUAUGCUCUUUAAAAACUACUGUAUAUAUGGACUCGUGAUUUCUUGCCAUUAGUAGUAAUAUAGUUGGUUCUAAUUUAAUAAAGAAUUGAAUUUUUGCUUCACAGGUCAAUUAGUAGAAACUAGUGAUACAUCUGAUCUCCUACAGAAAAUUUAAAUGAUGAUGAUAAGAUAAAAUGCUAAAAAUUUUCAGCGUUUGCUGAGUCUGCUAGGUACUGUGCUAAACCCAUUACAUGAAUUAUCUUAAUUUUAAUUUUCACAAAAACUCUGAGCCAGACCCUGUGUUUUCAUGUUAGAAGUAAAGAACCUAAGUCAGGUAGCCUUCUAAUUAUCAUCUUAUUCUAGUGCCUGAGAUAAAAUGAAUUUGAGGCAUUGACAAGUAACUGAUUGUAUUGGCCACAGGUAAACCAAAAUGUUCUUAUAAAAUUUGUUUAGUGUAUGUGGUUUAGAAACAAAAUCUUCAAAAACUUUAAUUUUGAAGCUCAAAUACUGCUUUAUCUCAUAUAGUGCCAAUCUGUCUCAAUAAUUGUUCAGUUCCUAUAUAUGAUCCAUAAUUGCCAUAUAGACACUAUAGACACAGCUUAAAUAAAUAAUGCAAAGCUUAAAUAAUGCAAUUAUACAUUUAAAAUAUAUCAUUUAUCAGUGUAUGAAUUUUACUUUAAAAAGAUAUUUAGUCCAGUCAAAGGAAAACCAAAUGAUAAACAAGGUGUUUUAUUUUACGUAUAUAAAUAUGUAACAUGGUAAACCAGGAACUCAGAUAGGGUUAGUAUCAUGCAAGUUAAGAAUCAAAUAGAAGGUAUUCCAUAUUUACCCUUUUCUCUUGUUUAUUAUUGAAAUCUCAACAUGAGGCAAUGUUCUUAGGAAGAAAUUUUAGUCUUUGAAUUAGAGUUUAAGAGAAGUUGCCUCUGUUUCUUUGAAUAAGGAAAAAACCCACAUAUUAAGUUAGCACUACUCUAUGCAUAGCAUGCUAUGUGUGCUACUCCAGGAACUAUGCUAGGUGCUUUAUGUGUAUAUUCUUGUUACUCUUUAUAACCCUGAUUUGAUAGGUAUCUCAUUUUACCUUUCAGAAUUUUGACUUUCAGAAGUUAAAGACUUUGCUCAAAGACAUACAGUUAAAAUGUGUUGUAGUCAGGACUCCAUAUAUAGUUCAUAAUUAUAUGAUACUUACUUAAAUGUAGUCCAGAUUCAUCUGUGACAAAUAAUUUUAAUAUAAUCACAUUUAAUGUCUUACAUUAAGAAGCAAAUUAAAAGAAAAAGUAAGAUCGUCAUUUUAGAAAUCCACUAAUAGCUAUCUGCCAAUUAAUUUACAUGGAAGGUGAUUAUAUUCUUAAAAGGAUUAUAACUGAGAAUGCAGCCCAGCGGGUCUCAGCCUUAUUUUGCCCAGCCCCUAUUCAAGAUGGAAUUGCUUUGGUUCAAACGCUUCUGACACUAACACUGUUUUUUAUAUAUAUAACAGAUCAAAGGAUAUAUAUAUAUAUAUAUAUAUUUCCAUGAUAAUCACCUGUGAAACUGUCAAACUUGAGGAAAAUGGUGCUUUACAAGUGAUGUAUUAGGAAUCUUAUUUUUAUAUUGUCUAAAGAAAAAUAAUUAUAUCUCAAAUAACACAAAAAACUCAUAAGGAAAUGUUGAAAAAUAUUUAAAAAUUUAAGUCACUAAAUUGCUAAUAUUUUUUUCAAAGAGUUAGCAAACACUUUAAAAUACAAGUUGUCACUAAUAUCAUAGAGCAGUCAACACUGUUGUUGAUUAAGUUUUUUCAGAUUACCUUUGUUAAACCAAAAUUAAAUAAUGUGAAAUUAUAAUUUAUGGAAAAUGCUGUCAUGGACCACAGCUUACAAGGAUGUCAUUUUUGUUUGGCUUAAUUUUUUCAUGAUUGAUUUCAGGGUUUAAAAUUUGGCAGAACUGUUAGCUUUUUUGGGGGGAGUAAAAGGAUAUACCAGGCUUAAAAAAUGGCUCAGUGGUACCAGGUUUAUAAACUUGAUUUCAGUAAAUUUUGAAAAUCUGAUGCUUGACUAUAGAAAUUAUUGCUUUAUGAUCAUGGAAUAAUUGGCAGUUGUUGAGGAAAAAUAUGGAGAUAAGUUCCAAAAGGAAGGGCAAGAUUUUUAUACUUGUGUUUAUGCUUAUAUAAUACUAUGUGAAAACUCAACUAUGAAAUAGUGGAGACACAUUUUAUUUGCCUUUUGAGAGAUUAAAACAAAGUUAUGAGACAUUAAAUGCCUUGCCCAGAGUGAUUAACAUGCAGGAGGAACUGAAACUCUGACCUUAUCUGCAACUGUAUAGCACUAUUAAAAUUGUUAAUAUUUUCUGAUAUACAGGUUAGGCUGAAAUAAUCAAGUCAUACAAAUUCUCAUGCAUUUAUUAUCUGAGAUAUACAUAUACCUACUCCCAAAAGAUUCUGCAUUAGAAUACAAGUACACAAUAUUUCACUUGUAAUUCCAAAAUCCAUAAUUUCUGAAACCAAGGUUUUAAGUAAGUUUGGCACUAAAAUGUGUUUGGAUAUGGAAACUGAUCCAAACUACCUGAAAUGAUUAAGUAUCCUUUACUUAUCCUAUUUAUUGUGAACAUAUAUGUUUUACUGCAGAACCAUUAAUUUCUCUGCUCCUUCAAACCCUACUGUGGAUGCUACACAUUAUGCGUUAUAUGCUCAGUAAUAUUUUCUAAAUCUGAAAAAUUUAGUUCUCAAACACAUCUAGCUCCAAGGGAUUGGGAGGUGAAAUAUGAGGACCCAUAUGCUUUGAGGAAACAGCUAAAGUGACAAUCUACACAUUCUGCUUGCUUUUAAUUAAUUUUUUGUAACUUUCUUCAAUAUAAUUUUUAAAAUAUAUUCACCUCCAAGUUGGACAAGCCGUGUGUUCUUUGGCAAGUCACAUCUCUCUGAACUUAUUGUCCACCAUCAAAUGAAGAUAAUAAAGUAUUUCCCAGGGGUAUGAUGUGUUAGUUAUAAUUGUCAAAUAAUAGAAUGCAAGUGAAAAGAUUUUUUAAUCUAUAAACUCUAUUGCAAAUGUGAAUAAUUUUUUUUCUGUUAAUAACUAACAUUAUUCCUCAAUAAUCUGUUUAGACUGACUCUCACGCUCACGAACAUUGCUCUUUGUUAUCUAUUGAUGGAUUUUAUGAUUAGCCCAUAAAAUGGUAUUUCUAGUAGUAUAUAUUGGCAAGUAAAUCUUCCUGAUGUGACUGCUGAUAAUAGGUACUAGCUGAUUUGGACGUGUAUUGUUAUAAAUUUCAUACUGUUAGUAAAAGAUGAAAAGCCAAGGGAAGAAUAAAAAGAAAUCCUUUUAAAUAAAACAAGAUAACUAACAGUGUCUAGGCUUGUCCUUUAUUAUACCCAAGAGAAAUUCUUAUUUUUUUGUCAAGGAAAUUAUAAUUUGCCUAAAAUAAUGAAUAGAGUAACCAAGAACUCUUUUAUAGCUAACAUGGUGACUUAGUUCUUAGUCAUUGUCUUUCUUAUGCAAAAGAAAUAAGCAAACUUAACAAGAAAGAAUUGUUAUUGUUACUCAAACUAUGAUAGAUUUAACAGCAGUAGUAAUAGUAGUGGUGAUGGUGGUAGUAGUAAUAAUAAGACCAUCAUCUUCUGUUUUCAGCUCAUAAGUUUUCGUAUUUUUUAACGAAUAAAUCAAAUAUUUUUCUCUAGUACAGAUUUCUUCACAGAUUUAUCCUAAAACGUAUUACCAACUGGGGAAAAGGAACUAUGGCUAGUUAUUUCUUUUAUAAUUUUUUGCAACUUUUAAUAAUUGGAAGGAAUAAUACAAGUAUUUGAGAUCAUGCUAAUGACUUCACUAACAAUUUACUAUUUCAGAAGGAAUUGGCACUGGAUUUUUAUUGUUUUUUGAGAUAUAUCAUUUAGCUUUUCCUAAUAUAAAUGAGUGUGUGUGUAUUUUCCCCAGAAAAUUAAUUAUAUUCUGUAUAAUUCUAUAUUUCCAGAACUCUCAGGGUUGGCCCUCAAAAACACAAGAAUGAAUACAUGGGGUUUGAUUUAUGUUAAUCUCAUUCUGUUCAUAGAACUUUAUUAGGAGUAAACAAACUAAUCUUUUUUCUUAAUAGAUAAAUCAAUAAAGCAUUCAAAAAGGGUAAUUGAUGAGUUAAUGAUAGGUAGUAAAUGAAAAUAUUUGAGCAAUAAAUUGUUCCUAUCUCCUUAAAUUAAAAUAUAAAGUUUUACUUUAUAGAGUUGUAUCAUAUCCUUCCUAGAGCAUUAAUUUUUCAAUGACACCAAUAUUUUGCAUAAUUUCUCACCAUACUUAAUUGCACUUAUACAUAUAUUUAAUCUUUACAACUGGAAAUUCAAGUGCUGUGUUUUGGCACAUGUGUAGGAAAAAAGAGGCCAAUUUGAAUCAAAUAAAAUUUUUUUGUUAUUGAAAUAA